CUCAGAGGCUGCUGAGGGACAGGGCACUCUUCCCCGCCGUCCACACAAUGAGUGUUGGCCGGAGGAAGCUGGCCCUGCUCUGGGCCCUGGCUCUCGCUCUGGCCUGCACCCGGCAUACAGGCCAUGCCCAGGAUGGCUCCUCCGAAUCCAGCUACAAGCACCACCCUGCCCUCUCUCCUAUCGCCCGGGGGCCCAGCGGGGUCCCGCUCCGUGGGGCGACUGUCUUCCCAUCUCUGAGGACCAUCCCUGUGGUACGAGCCUCCAACCCGGCGCACAACGGGCGGGUGUGCAGCACCUGGGGCAGCUUCCACUACAAGACCUUCGACGGCGACGUCUUCCGCUUCCCCGGCCUCUGCAACUACGUGUUCUCCGAGCACUGCGGUGCCGCCUACGAGGAUUUUAACAUCCAGCUACGCCGCAGCCAGGAGUCAGCGGCCCCCACGCUGAGCAGGGUCCUCAUGAAGGUGGAUGGCGUGGUCAUCCAGCUGACCAAGGGCUCCGUCCUGGUCAACGGCCACCCGGUCCUGCUGCCCUUCAGCCAGUCUGGGGUCCUCAUUCAGCAGAGCAGCAGCUACACCAAGGUGGAGGCCAGGCUGGGCCUUGUCCUCAUGUGGAACCACGAUGACAGCCUGCUGCUGGAGCUGGACACCAAAUACGCCAACAAGACCUGUGGGCUCUGUGGGGACUUCAACGGGAUGCCCGUGGUCAGCGAGCUCCUCUCCCACAACACCAAGCUGACACCCAUGGAAUUCGGGAACCUGCAGAAGAUGGACGACCCCACGGACCAGUGUCAGGACCCUGUCCCUGAACCCCCGAGGAACUGCUCCACUGGCUUUGGCAUCUGUGAGGAGCUCCUGCACGGCCAGCUGUUCUCUGGCUGCGUGGCCCUGGUGGACGUCGGCAGCUACCUGGAGGCUUGCAGGCAAGACCUCUGCUUCUGUGAAGACACCGACCUGCUCAGCUGCGUCUGCCACACCCUUGCCGAGUACUCCCGGCAGUGCACCCAUGCAGGGGGGUUGCCCCAGGACUGGCGGGGCCCUGACUUCUGCCCCCAGAAGUGCCCCAACAACAUGCAGUACCACGAGUGCCGCUCCCCCUGCGCAGACACCUGCUCCAACCAGGAGCACUCCCGGGCCUGUGAGGACCACUGUGUGGCCGGCUGCUUCUGCCCUGAGGGGACGGUGCUUGACGACAUCGGCCAGACCGGCUGUGUCCCUGUGUCAAAGUGUGCCUGCGUCUACAACGGGGCUGCCUAUGCCCCAGGGGCCACCUACUCCACAGACUGCACCAACUGCACCUGCUCCGGAGGCCGGUGGAGCUGCCAGGAGGUUCCAUGCCCGGGUACCUGCUCUGUGCUUGGAGGUGCCCACUUCUCAACGUUUGACGGGAAGCAAUACACGGUGCACGGCGACUGCAGCUAUGUGCUGACCAAGCCCUGUGACAGCAGUGCCUUCACUGUACUGGCUGAGCUGCGCAGGUGCGGGCUGACGGACAGCGAGACCUGCCUGAAGAGCGUGACACUGAGCCUGGAUGGGGCGCAGACGGUGGUGGUGAUCAAGGCCAGUGGGGAAGUGUUCCUGAACCAGAUCUACACCCAGCUGCCCAUCUCUGCAGCCAACGUCACCAUCUUCAGACCCUCAACCUUCUUCAUCAUCGCCCAGACCAGCCUGGGCCUGCAGCUGAACCUGCAGCUGGUGCCCACCAUGCAGCUGUUCAUGCAGCUGGCGCCCAAGCUCCGUGGGCAGACCUGCGGUCUCUGUGGGAACUUCAACAGCAUCCAGGCCGAUGACUUCCGGACCCUCAGUGGGGUGGUGGAGGCCACCGCUGCGGCCUUCUUCAACACCUUCAAGACCCAGGCCGCCUGCCCCAACAUCAGGAACAGCUUCGAGGACCCCUGCUCUCUGAGCGUGGAGAAUGAGAAGUAUGCUCAGCACUGGUGCUCGCAGCUGACCGAUGCCGACGGCCCCUUCGGCCGGUGCCAUGCUGCCGUGAAGCCGGGAACCUACUACUCGAACUGCAUGUUUGACACCUGCAACUGUGAGCGGAGCGAGGACUGCCUGUGCGCCGCGCUGUCCUCCUACGUGCACGCCUGUGCCGCCAAGGGCGUGCAGCUCGGCGGCUGGAGGGACGGCGUCUGCACGAAGCCUAUGACCACUUGCCCCAAGUCAAUGACGUACCACUACCAUGUCAGCACCUGCCAGCCCACCUGCCGCUCCCUGAGCGAGGGGGACAUCACCUGCAGUGUUGGCUUCAUCCCCGUGGAUGGCUGCAUCUGUCCCAAGGGCACCUUCCUGGACGACACGGGCAAGUGUGUGCAGGCCAGCAACUGUCCCUGCUACCACAGAGGCUCCAUGAUCCCCAAUGGGGAGUCGGUGCACGACAGCGGGGCUAUCUGCACCUGCACACAUGGGAAGCUGAGCUGCAUCGGAGGCCAAGCCCCCGCCCCAGUGUGUGCUGCGCCCAUGGUGUUCUUUGACUGCCGAAAUGCCACGCCCGGGGACACAGGGGCUGGCUGUCAGAAGAGCUGCCACACACUGGACAUGACCUGUUACAGCCCCCAGUGUGUGCCUGGCUGCGUGUGCCCCGACGGGCUGGUGGCGGACGGCGAGGGCGGCUGCAUCACUGCGGAGGACUGCCCCUGCGUGCACAAUGAGGCCAGCUACCGGGCCGGCCAGACCAUCCGGGUGGGCUGCAACACCUGCACCUGUGACAGCAGGAUGUGGCGGUGCACAGAUGACCCCUGCCUGGCCACCUGCGCCGUGUACGGGGACGGCCACUACCUCACCUUCGACGGACAGAGCUACAGCUUCAACGGAGACUGCGAGUACACGCUGGUGCAGAACCACUGUGGCGGGAAAGACAGCACCCAGGACUCCUUUCGUGUUGUCACCGAGAACGUCCCCUGCGGCACCACAGGGACCACCUGCUCCAAGGCCAUCAAGAUUUUCCUGGGGGGCUUCGAGCUGAAGCUAAGCCAUGGGAAGGUGGAGGUGAUCGGGACGGACGAGAGCCAGGAGGUGCCAUACACCAUCCGGCAGAUGGGCAUCUACCUGGUGGUGGACACCGACAUUGGCCUGGUGCUGCUGUGGGACAAGAAGACCAGCAUCUUCAUCAACCUCAGCCCCGAGUUCAAGGGCAGGGUCUGCGGCCUGUGUGGGAACUUCGACGACAUCGCCGUUAAUGACUUUGCCACGCGGAGCCGGUCUGUGGUGGGGGACGUGCUGGAGUUUGGGAACAGCUGGAAGCUCUCCCCCUCCUGCCCAGAUGCCCUGGCGCCCAAGGACCCCUGCACGGCCAACCCCUUCCGCAAGUCCUGGGCCCAGAAGCAGUGCAGCAUCCUCCACGGCCCCACCUUCGCCGCCUGCCACGCACACGUGGAGCCGGCCAGGUACUACGAGGCCUGCGUGAACGACGCGUGCGCCUGCGACUCCGGGGGUGACUGCGAGUGCUUCUGCACGGCUGUGGCCGCCUACGCCCAGGCCUGCCAUGAAGUAGGCCUGUGUGUGUCCUGGCGGACCCCGAGCAUCUGCCCUCUGUUCUGCGACUACUACAACCCCGAAGGCCAGUGCGAGUGGCACUACCAGCCCUGCGGGGUGCCCUGCCUGCGCACCUGCCGGAACCCCCGUGGAGACUGCCUGCGGGACGUCCGGGGCCUGGAAGGCUGCUACCCCAAGUGCCCACCAGAGGCUCCCAUCUUUGAUGAGGACAAGAUGCAGUGUGUGGCCACCUGCCCAACCCCGCCUCUGCCACCACGGUGCCACGUCCAUGGGAAGUCCUACCGGCCAGGUGCAGUGGUGCCCUCGGACAAGAACUGCCAGUCCUGCCUUUGUACGGAGCGCGGCGUGGAGUGCACCUACAAAGCUGAGGCCUGUGUCUGCACCUACAAUGGACAGCGCUUCCACCCAGGGGACGUCAUCUACCACACGACGGAUGGCACGGGUGGCUGCAUCUCCGCCCGCUGCGGGGCCAACGGCACCAUUGAGAGGAGGGUCUACCCCUGCAGCCCCACCACCCCUGUCCCCCCAACCACCUUCUCCUUCUCCACACCCCCGCUUGUCGUGAGCUCCACGCACACCCCCAGCAAUGGCCCAAGCAGCGCGCACACAGGCCCUCCGAGCAGCGCCUGGCCCACCACAGCAGGCACUUCUCCCAGGACGAGGCUGCCCACAGCCUCUGCCUCACUGCCGCCGGUCUGUGGGGAAAAGUGCCUGUGGUCGCCAUGGAUGGAUGUCAGCCGCCCUGGACGGGGCACGGACAGCGGUGACUUCGACACACUGGAGAACCUCCGCGCCCAUGGGUACCGGGUGUGCGAAUCACCCAGGUCGGUGGAGUGCCGAGCUGAGGACGCCCCCGGAGUGCCGCUCCGAGCCCUGGGGCAGCGUGUGCAGUGCAGCCCGGAUGUGGGGCUGACCUGUCGUAACAGGGAGCAGGCAUCGGGGCUCUGCUACAACUACCAGAUCAGGGUCCAGUGCUGCACGCCCCUACCCUGCUCCACCUCUAGCAGUCCAGCCCAGACCACUCCUCCAACUACCUCCAAGACCACUGAAACCCGGGCCUCAGGCUCCUCAGCUCCCAGCAGCACACCUGGCACCGUGUCUCUCUCUACAGCCAGGACGACACCUGCCCCAGGUACCGCUACCUCUGUCAAAAAAACUUUCUCAACUCCCAGCCCUCCGCCAGUGCCGGCAACAUCAACAUCAUCCAUGUCGACCACGGCCCCGGGGACCUCUGUGGUCUCCAGCAAGCCCACCCCCACGGAGCCCAGCACAUCCUCCUGCCUGCAGGAGCUUUGCACCUGGACCGAGUGGAUCGAUGGCAGCUACCCUGCUCCUGGAAUAAAUGGUGGAGAUUUUGACACAUUUCAAAAUUUGAGAGACGAAGGAUACACAUUCUGUGAAAGUCCUCGAAGCGUGCAGUGCCGGGCAGAGAGCUUCCCCAACACGCCGCUGGCAGACCUGGGGCAGGACGUCAUCUGCAGCCACACAGAGGGGCUGAUUUGCCUGAACAAGAACCAGCUCCCACCCAUCUGCUACAACUAUGAGAUCCGCAUCCAGUGUUGCGAGACGGUGAACGUGUGCAGAGACAUCACCAGACUGCCAAAGACCGUCGCAACGACACGGCCGACUCCACAUCCAACCGGAGCUCAGACCCAGACCACCUUCACCACACACAUGCCCUCGGCCUCCACAGAGCAACCCACGGCAACCUCCAGGGGUGGGCCCACAGCAACCAGCGUCACACAGGGCACCCACACCACACUAGUCACCAGAAACUGUCAUCCCCGGUGCACCUGGACAAAGUGGUUCGACGUGGACUUCCCGUCCCCCGGACCCCAUGGUGGAGACAAGGAAACCUACAACAACAUCAUCAGGAGUGGGGAAAAAAUCUGCCGCCGACCUGAGGAGAUCACCAGGCUCCAGUGCCGAGCCAAGAGCCACCCAGAGGUGAGCAUCGAACACCUGGGCCAGGUGGUGCAGUGCAGCCGGGAAGAGGGCCUGGUGUGCCGGAACCAGGACCAGCAGGGACCCUUCAAGAUGUGCCUCAACUACGAGGUGCGUGUGCUCUGCUGCGAGACCCCCAGAGGCUGCCACAUGACCUCCACACCUGGCUCCACCUCUAGCAGUCCAGCCCAGACCACUCCUUCAACAACCUCCAAGACCACUGAAACCCAGGCCUCAGGCUCCUCAGCCCCCAGCAGCACACCUGGCACCGUGUCUCUCUCUACAGCCAGGACGACACCUGCCCCAGGUACCGCUACCUCUGUCAAAAAAACUUUCUCAACUCCCAGCCCUCCGCCAGUGCCGGCAACAUCAACAUCAUCCAUGUCGACCACGGCCCCGGGGACCUCUGUGGUCUCCAGCAAGCCCACCCCCACGGAGCCCAGCACAUCCUCCUGCCUGCAGGAGCUUUGCACCUGGACCGAGUGGAUUGAUGGCAGCUACCCUGCUCCUGGAAUAAAUGGUGGAGAUUUUGACACAUUUCAAAAUUUGAGAGACGAAGGAUACACAUUCUGUGAAAGUCCUCGAAGCGUGCAGUGCCGGGCAGAGAGCUUCCCCAACACGCCGCUGGCAGACCUGGGGCAGGACGUCAUCUGCAGCCACACAGAGGGGCUGAUUUGCCUGAACAAGAACCAGCUCCCACCCAUCUGCUACAACUAUGAGAUCCGCAUCCAGUGUUGCGAGACGGUGAACGUGUGCAGAGACAUCACCAGACCGCCAAAGACCGUCGCAACGACACGGCCGACUCCACAUCCAACCGGAGCUCAGACCCAGACCACCUUCACCACACACAUGCCCUCGGCCUCCACAGAGCAACCCACGGCAACCUCCAGGGGUGGGCCCACAGCAACCAGCGUCACACAGGGCACCCACACCACACCAGUCACCAGAAACUGUCAUCCCCGGUGCACCUGGACAACGUGGUUCGACGUGGACUUCCCGUCCCCCGGACCCCAUGGUGGAGACAAGGAAACCUACAACAACAUCAUCAGGAGUGGGGAAAAAAUCUGCCGCCGACCUGAGGAGAUCACCAGGCUCCAGUGCCGAGCCAAGAGCCACCCAGAGGUGAGCAUCGAACACCUGGGCCAGGUGGUGCAGUGCAGCCGGGAAGAGGGCCUGGUGUGCCGGAACCAGGACCAGCAGGGACCCUUCAAGAUGUGCCUCAACUACGAGGUGCGUGUGCUCUGCUGCGAGACCCCCAAAGGCUGCCCCGUGACCUCCACACCUGUGACAGCUCCUAGCACCCCUAGUGGGAGAGCCACCAGCCCAACUCAGAGCACCUCCUCUUGGCAGAAAUCCAGGACAACCACUUUGGUGACAACCAGCACAACCUCCACUCCACAGACCAGUACAACCUAUGCCCAUACAACCAGCACAACCUCUGCUCCUACAGCCAGAACAACCUCUGCUCCUACAACCAGAACAACCUCUGCCUCUCCAGCCAGCACAACCUCUGGUCCUGGAAAUACUCCCAGCCCUGUUCCUACCACCAGCACAAUCUCUGCUCCUACAACUAGCAUAACCUCUGCCCCUACAACCAGCACAACCUCUGCCCCUACAAGCAGCACAACCUCUGGUCCUGGAACUACUCCCAGCCCUGUUCCUACCACCAGCAUAACCUCUGCCCCUACAACCAGCACAACCUCUGCUCCUACAACCAGCACAACCUCUGCCCGUACAAGCAGCACAACCUCUGCCACUACCACCAGCAGAAUCUCUGGUCCUGAAACUACUCCCAGCCCUGUUCCUACCACCAGCACAACCUCUGCCACUACAACCAGCACAACCUCAGCUCCUACAACCAGCACAACCUCUGCCCCUACAAGCAGCACAACCUCCAGUCCACAGACCAGCACAACCUCGGCUCCUACAACCAGCACAACUUCUGGUCCUGGAACUACCCCAAGCCCUGUUCCCACGACCAGCACAACCUCUGCCCCUACAACAAGAACAACUUCUGCUCCUAAAAGCAGCACAACCUCUGCCGCUACAACCAGCACAACCUCUGGUCCUGAAACUACUCCUAGACCUGUUCCUACCACCAGCACAACCUCUUCUCCUACAACCAGCACAACCUCUGCUCCUACAACCAGCACAACCUCUGCUUCUACAACCAGCACAACCUCUGGUGCUGGAACUACUCCCAGCCCUGUUCCCACCACCAGCACAACCUCUGCUCCUACAACCAGCACAACCUCUGCCCCUAUAAGCAGCACAACCUCUGCCACUACAACCAGCACAACCUCUGGUCCUGGAACUACUCCCAGCCCUGUUCCUACCACGAGCACAACCUCUGCUCCUACAACCAGCACAACCUCUGGUCCUGGAACUACUCCCAGUGCUGUUCCCACCACCAGCAUAACCUCUGCACCUACAACCAGCACAAACUCUGCCCCUAUAAGCAGCACAACCUCUGCCACUACAACCAGCAGAAUCUCUGGUCCUGAAACUACUCCCAGCCCUGUUCCUACCGCCAGCACAACCUCUGCUUCUACAACUAGCACAACCUCUGGUCCUGGAACUACUCCCAGCCCUGUUCCUACCACCAGCACAAUCUCUGUUCCUACCACCAGCACAACUUCUGCUUCUACAACCAGCACAACCUCUGCUUCUACAACCAGCACAACCUCUGGUCCUGGAACUACUCCCAGCCCUGUUCCCACCACCAGCACAACCUCUGCUCCCACAACAAGCACAACCUCUGCCCCUACAACCAGCACAAUCUCGGCCCCAACAACCAGCACAACCUCUGCCACUACAACCAGCACGACCUCUGCUCCUACACCCAGAAGAACCUCAGCCCCUACAACCAGCACAAUCUCUGCCUCUACCACCAGCACAACCUCUGCGACUACAACCAGCACAACCUCUGCUACUACAACCAGCACAAUCUCUGCCCCUACAACCAGCACAACUUUGUCUCCUACAACCAGCACAACCUCUACUACUAUAACCAGCACAACUUCUGCCCCUAUAAGCAGCACAACUUCCACACCACAGACCAGCACAACUUCGGCUCCUACAACCAGCACAACUUCUGGUCCUGGAACUACUUCAAGCCCUGUUCCCACCACCAGCACAACCUCUGCCCCUACAACCAGCACAACCUCUGCCCCUACAACCAGAACAACCUCUGUCCCUACAAGCAGCACAACCUCCACUGCUACAACCAGCACAACCUCUGGCCCUGGAACUACUCCCAGCCCUGUUCCCACCACCAGUACAACCUCUGCUCCUACAACCAGAACAACCUCUGCUCCUACAACCAGCACAACCUCUGCCCCUACAACCAGCACAACCUCUGCCCCUACAAGCAGCACAACCUCAGCUACUACAACCAGCACAAUCUCUGUUCCUACAACCAGCACAACUUCUGUUCCUGGAACUACUCCCAGCCCUGUUCCUACCACCAGCACAAUCUCUGUUCCUACCACCAGCACAACUUCUGCUUCUACAACCAGCACAACCUCUGGUCCUGGAACUACUCCCAGCCCUGUUCCCACCACCAGCACAACCUCUGCUCCCACAACAAGCACAACCUCUGCCCCUACAACCAGCACAAUCUCGGCCCCAACAACCAGCACACCCUCUGCCCCUACAACCAGCACAACCUUAGCUCCUACAACCAGCACAACCUCUGCCCCUACAACCAGCACAACCUCUACCCCUACAAGCAGCACAACCUCCUCUCCACAGACCAGCACAACCUCGGCUUCUACCACCAGCAUAACUUCUGGUCCUGGAACUACCCCAAGCCCUGUUCCCACCACCAGCACAACCUCUGCUCCUACAACCAGCACAACCUCUGCCGCUACAACCAGCACAAUCUCGGCCCCAACAACCAGCACAACGUCUGCUCCUACAACCAGCACAACCUCUGCCUCUACAGCCAGCAAAACCUCUGGUCUUGGAACUACUCCCAGCCCUAUUCCUACCACCAGCACAACCUCUCCUCCUACAACCAGCACAACUUCUGCCUCUACAGCCAGCAAAACCUCUGGUCCUGGAACCACUCCCAGCCCUGUUCCCACCACCAGCACAAUCUUUGCUCCUAGAACCAGCACCACUUCUGCCUCUACAACCAGCACAACCCCUGGUCCUGGAACCACUCCCAGCCCCGUUCCCACCACCAGCACAGCCUCUGUUUCAAAGACCAGCACAAGCCAUGUUUCCAUAUCCAAGACAACCCACUCCCAACCAGUCACCAGAGACUGUCAUCUCCGGUGCACCUGGACCAAGUGGUUUGACAUAGACUUCCCAUCCCCUGGACCCCACGGCGGGGACAAGGAAACCUACAACAACAUCAUCAGGAGUGGGGAAAAAAUCUGCCGCCGACCUGAGGAGAUCACCAGGCUCCAGUGCCGAGCCGAGAGCCACCCGGAGGUGAGCAUUGAACACCUGGGCCAGGUGGUGCAGUGCAGCCGUGAAGAGGGCCUGGUGUGCCGGAACCAGGACCAGCAGGGACCCUUCAAGAUGUGCCUCAACUACGAGGUGCGUGUGCUCUGCUGCGAGACCCCUAAAGGUUGCCCCGUGACCUCCACACCUGUGACAGCUCCUAGCACCCCUAGUGGGAGAGCCACCAGCCCAACUCAGAGCACUUCCUCUUGGCAGAAAUCCAGGACAACCACUUUGGUGACAACCAGCACAACCUCCACUCCACAGACCAGCACAACCUCUGCUCCUACAACCAGCACAACCUCUGCUCCCACAACCAGCACAACUUCUGCCCCUACAACCAGCACAACCUCCACUCCACAGACCAGCAUAUCCUCUGCCCCUACAAGCAGCACAACCUCGGCUCCUACAAGCAGCACAAUCUCUGCUCGUACAACCAGCAUAAUCUCUGCCCCUACAACCAGCACAACCUCUUCCCCUACAACCAGCACAACCUCUGCUACUACAACCAGCACAACCUCUGCCCCUACAAGCAGCACAACCUCCACUCCACAGACCAGCAAAACCUCAGCUGCUACAAGCAGCACAACCUCCGGUUCUGGAACUACUCCCAGCCCUGUUACCACCACCAGCACAGCCUCUGUUUCAAAGACCAGCACAAGCCAUGUUUCUGUAUCCAAGACAACCCACUCCCAACCAGUCACCAGAGACUGUCAUCCCCGGUGCACCUGGACCAAAUGGUUUGAUGUGGACUUUCCAUCCCCUGGACCCCACGGUGGGGACAAGGAAACCUACAACAACAUCAUCAGGAGUGGGGAAAAAAUCUGCCGCCGACCUGAGGAGAUCACCAGGCUCCAGUGCCGAGCCAAGAGCCACCCGGAGGUGAGCAUCGAACACCUGGGCCAGGUGGUGCAGUGCAGCCGCGAAGAGGGCCUGGUGUGCCGGAACCAGGACCAGCAGGGACCCUUCAAGAUGUGCCUCAACUACGAGGUGCGUGUGCUUUGCUGCGAGACCCCCAAAGGCUGCCCCGUGACCUCCACAUCUGUGACAGCUCCUAGCACCCCUAGUGGGAGAGCCACCAGCCCAACUCAGAGCACCUCCUCUUGGCAGAAAUCCAGGACAACCACUUUGGUGACAAGCAGCAUAACCUCCACUACACAGACCAGCACAACCUCUGCCCCUACAACUAGCACAACCCCUGCUUCUAUACCCAGCACAACCUCUGCCCCAACAACCAGCACAACCUCUGCUCCCACAACGAGCACAACUUCUGCCCCUACAACCAGCACAACCUCCACUCCACAGACCACCACAUCCUCUGCCCCUACAAGCAGCACAACCUCGGCUCCUACCACCAGCACAAUCUCUGCCCCUACAACCAGCACAAUCUCUGCCCCUACAACCAGCACAACCUCUGCUCCCACAGCCAGCACAACGUCAGCUCCUACGAGCACUUCCUCGGCUCCUACAACCAACACAACCUCUGCCCCUACAACUAGCACUACCUCUGCUCCCAUAACCAGCACAAUCUCUGCCCCUACAACCAGCACAACCUCCACUCCACAGACCAGCACAAUCUCUUCCCCUACAACCAGCACAACCUCCACUCCGCAGACCAGCACAACCUCUUCCCCUACAACUAGCACAACCUCAGCUCCUACAACCAGCACAACUUCUGCCCCUACAACCAGCACAACCUCCACUCCACAGACCAGCAUAUCCUCUGCCCCUACAAGCAGCACAACCUCUGCUCCUACAGCCAGCACAAUCUCUGCCCCUACAACCAGCACAACCUCUUUCCAUACAACCAGCACAACCUCUCCCCCUACAAGCAGCACAAGCUCCACUCCACAGACCAGCAAAACCUCAGCUGCUACAAGCAGCACAACCUCCGGUUCUGGAACUACUCCCAGCCCCGUUCCCACCACCAGCACAGCCUCUGUUUCAAAGACCAGCACAAGCCAUGUUUCUGUAUCCAAGACAACCCACUCCCAACCAGUCACCAGAGACUGUCAUCCCCGGUGCACCUGGACCAAGUGGUUUGACGUGGACUUUCCAUCCCCUGGACCCCACGGUGGGGACAAGGAAACCUACAACAACAUCAUCAGGAGUGGGGAAAAAAUCUGCCGCCGACCUGAGGAGAUCACCAGGCUCCAGUGCCGAGCCGAGAGCCACCCGGAGGUGAGCAUCGAACACCUGGGCCAGGUGGUGCAGUGCAGCCGGGAAGAGGGCCUGGUGUGCCGGAACCAGGACCAGCAGGGACCCUUCAAGAUGUGCCUCAACUACGAGGUGCGUGUGCUCUGCUGCGAGACCCCCAAAGGCUGCCCCGUGACCUCCACACCUGUGACAGCUCCUAGCACCCCUAGUGGGAGAGCCACCAGCCCAACUCAGAGCACUUCCUCUUGGCAGAAAUCCAGGACAACCACUUUGGUGACAACCAGCACAACCUCCACUCCACAGACCAGCACAACCUCUGCCCCUACAACCAGCACAAUCCCUGCUUCUACACCCAGCACAACCUCUGCCCCUACAACCAGCACAACCUCUGCCCCUACAACCAGCACGACCUCAGCUCCUACACACAGAACGACUUCUGGUCCUACAACCAGCACAACCUUGGCUCCUACAACCAGCACAACCUCUGCUCCAACAACCAGCACAAACUCUGCUCCUACAACCAGCACAAUCUCUGCCUCUACAACCAGCACAAUCUCUGCCCCUACAACCAGCACAAUCUCUUCCCCUACAAGCAGCACAACCUCCACUCCACAGACCAGCAAAACCUCAGCUGCUACAAGCAGCACAACCUCCGGUUCUGGAACUACUCCAAGCCCUGUUCCCACCACCAGCACAACCUCUGCCUCUACAACCAGCACAACUUCUGCUCCUACAACCAGCACAACCUCUGGUCCUGGAACUACUCCAAGCCCUGUUCCCAGCACCAGUACAACCUCUGCUGCUACAACCAGCACAACCUCUGCUCCUACAACCAGAACAACAUCUGCUCCUACAAGCAGCAUGACCUCUGGUCCUGGAACUACUCCCAGCCCUGUUCCCACCACCAGCACAACCUCUGCUCCUACAACUAGCACAACCUCUGGUCCUGGAACUACUCCCAGCCCUGUUCCCACCACCAGCACAACCUCUGCUCCUAUAACCAGCACAACCUCUGGUCCUGGAAGUACUCCCAGCCCUGUUCCCACCACCAGCACAACCUCUGCUCCUACAACCAGCACAACCUCUGCCUCUACAGCCAGCACAACCUCUGGUCCUGGAACUACUCCCAGCCCUGUUCCCACCACCAGCACAACCUCUGCUCCUACAACCAGAACAACCUCUGCCUCUACAGCCAGCACAACCUCUGGUCCUGGAAGUACUCCCAGCCCUGUUCCCACCACCAGCACAACCUCUGCUCCUACAACCAGAACAACCCCUGCCUCUACAGCCAGCACAACCUCUGGUCCUGGAACUACUCCCAGCCCUGUUCCCACCACAAGCACAACCUCUGCUUCUACAACCAGCACAAUCUCUCUCCCUACAACCAGCACAACCUCUGCUCCUAUAACCAGCAUGACCUCUGGUCCUGGAACUACUCCCAGCCCUGUUCCCACCACCAGCACAACCUCUGCUCCUACAACCAGCACAACCUCUGCCUCUACAGCCAGCACAACCUCUGGUCCUGGAACUACUCCCAGCCCUGUUCCCACCACCAGCACAACCUCUGCUCCUACAACCAGCACAACCUCUGCCUCUACAGCCAGCACAACCUCUGGUCCUGGAACUUCUCUCAGCCCUGUUCCCACCACGAGCACAACCUCUGCUCCUACAACUAGCACAACCUCUGGUCCUGGAACUACUCCCAGCCCUGUUCCCACCACCAGCACAACCUCUGCUCCUACAACCAGCACGACCUCUGGUCCUGGAACUACUCCCAGCCCCGUUCCCACCACCAGCACAACCCCUGUUUCAAAGACCAGCACAAGCCAUCUUUCUGUAUCCAAGACAACCCACUCCCAACCAGUCACCAGUGACUGUCAUCCUCUGUGCGCCUGGACAAAGUGGUUCGACGUGGACUUCCCAUCCCCUGGACCCCACGGCGGGGACAAGGAAACCUACAACAACAUCAUCAGGAGUGGGGAAAAAAUCUGCCGCCGACCUGAGGAGAUCACCAGGCUCCAGUGCCGAGCCGAGAGCCACCCGGAGGUGAACAUUGAACACCUGGGUCAGGUGGUGCAGUGCAGCCGUGAAGAGGGCCUGGUGUGCCGGAACCAGGACCAGCAGGGACCCUUCAAGAUGUGCCUCAACUACGAGGUGCGCGUGCUCUGCUGCGAGACCCCCAGAGGCUGCCCGGUGACCUCUGUGACCCCAUAUGGGACUUCUCCUACCAAUGCUCUGUAUCCUUCCCUGUCUACUUCCAUGGUAUCCGCCUCCGUGGCAUCCACCUCUGUGGCAUCCAGCUCUGUGGCAUCCAGCUCUGUGGCUUACUCCACCCAAACCUGCUUCUGCAACGUGGCUGACCGGCUCUACCCUGCAGGAUCCACCAUAUACCGCCACAGAGACCUCGCUGGCCAUUGCUAUUAUGCCCUGUGUAGCCAGGACUGCCAAGUGGUCAGAGGGGUUGACAGUGACUGUCCGUCCACCACGCUGCCUCCUGCCCCAGCCACGUCCCCUUCAAUAUCCACCUCCGAGCCCGUCACUGAGCUGGGAUGCCCAAAUGCGGUUCCCCCCAGAAAGAAAGGUGAGACCUGGGCCACACCCAACUGCUCCGAGGCCACCUGUGAGGGCAACAACGUCAUCUCCCUGCGCCCGCGCACGUGCCCGAGGGUGGAGAAGCCCACUUGUGCCAACGGCUACCCGGCUGUGAAGGUGGCUGACCAAGAUGGCUGCUGCCAUCACUACCAGUGCCAGUGUGUGUGCAGCGGCUGGGGUGACCCCCACUACAUCACCUUCGACGGCACCUACUACACCUUCCUGGACAACUGCACGUACGUGCUGGUGCAGCAGAUUGUGCCCGUGUAUGGCCACUUCCGCGUGCUCGUCGACAACUACUUCUGCGGUGCGGAGGACGGGCUCUCCUGCCCGAGGUCCAUCAUCCUGGAGUACCACCAGGACCGCGUGGUGCUGACCCGCAAGCCAGUCCACGGGGUGAUGACAAACGAGAUCAUCUUCAACAACAAGGUGGUCAGCCCCGGCUUCCGGAAAAACGGCAUCGUGGUCUCGCGCAUCGGCGUCAAGAUGUACGCGACCAUCCCGGAGCUGGGAGUCCAGGUCAUGUUCUCCGGCCUCAUCUUCUCCGUGGAGGUGCCCUUCAGCAAGUUUGCCAACAACACCGAGGGCCAGUGCGGCACUUGCACCAACGACAGGAAGGAUGAGUGCCGCACGCCUAGGGGGACGGUGGUCGCUUCCUGCUCCGAGAUGUCCGGCCUCUGGAACGUGAGCAUACCCGACCAGCCAGCCUGCCACCGGCCUCACCCGACGCCCACCACGGUCGGGCCCACCACAGUUGGGUCUACCACGGUCGGGCCCACCACAGUUGGGUCUACCACGGUCGGGCCCACCACACCGCCUGCUCCGUGCCUGCCAUCACCCAUCUGCCAGCUGAUUCUGAGCAAGGUCUUUGAGCCGUGCCACACUGUGAUCCCCCCACUGCUGUUCUAUGAGGGCUGCGUCUUUGACCGGUGCCACAUGACGGACCUGGAUGUGGUGUGCUCCAGCCUGGAGCUGUACGCGGCACUCUGUGCGUCCCACGACAUCUGCAUCGAUUGGAGAGGCCGGACCGGCCACAUGUGCCCAUUCACCUGCCCAGCCGACAAGGUGUACCAGCCCUGCGGCCCGAGCAACCCCUCCUACUGCUACGGGAAUGACAGCGCCAGCCUCGGGGCUCUGCCGGAGGCCGGCCCCAUCACCGAAGGCUGCUUCUGUCCGGAGGGCAUGACCCUCUUCAGCACCAGUGCCCAAGUCUGCGUGCCCACGGGCUGCCCCAGGUGUCUGGGGCCCCACGGAGAGCCGGUGAAGGUGGGCCACACCGUCGGCAUGGACUGCCAGGAGUGCACGUGUGAGGCGGCCACGUGGACGCUGACCUGCCGACCCAAGCUCUGCCCGCUGCCCCCUGCCUGCCCCCUGCCCGGCUUCGUGCCUGUGCCUGCAGCCCCACAGGCCGGCCAGUGCUGCCCCCAGUACAGCUGCGCCUGCAACACCAGCCGCUGCCCCGCGCCCGUGGGCUGUCCUGAGGGCGCCCGCGCGAUCCCGACCUACCAGGAGGGGGCCUGCUGCCCAGUCCAAAACUGCAGCUGGACAGUGUGCAGCAUCAACGGGACCCUGUACCAGCCCGGCGCCGUGGUCUCCUCGAGCCUGUGCGAAACCUGCAGGUGUGAGCUGCCGGGUGGCCCCCCAUCGGACGCGUUUGUGGUCAGCUGUGAGACCCAGAUCUGCAACACACACUGCCCUGUGGGCUUCGAGUACCAGGAGCAGAGCGGGCAGUGCUGUGGCACCUGUGUGCAGGUCGCCUGUGUCACCAACACCAGCAAGAGCCCCGCCCACCUCUUCUACCCCGGCGAGACCUGGUCAGACGCAGGGAACCACUGUGUGACCCACCAGUGUGAGAAGCACCAGGAUGGGCUCGUGGUGGUCACCACGAAGAAGGCGUGCCCCCCGCUCAGCUGUUCUCUGGACGAGGCCCGCAUGAGCAAGGACGGCUGCUGCCGCUUCUGCCCGCCGCCCCCGCCCCCGUACCAGAACCAGUCGACCUGUGCUGUGUACCAUAGGAGCCUGAUCAUCCAGCAGCAGGGCUGCAGCUCCUCGGAGCCCGUGCGCCUGGCUUACUGCCGGGGGAACUGUGGGGACAGCUCUUCCAUGUACUCGCUCGAGGGCAACACGGUGGAGCACAGGUGCCAGUGCUGCCAGGAGCUGCGGACCUCGCUGAGGAAUGUGACCCUGCACUGCACCGACGGCUCCAGCCGGGCCUUCAGCUACACCGAGGUGGAAGAGUGCGGCUGCAUGGGCCGGCGGUGCCCUGCGCCGGGCGACACCCAGCACUCGGAGGAGGCGGAACCCGAGCCCAGCCAGGAGGCAGAGAGUGGGAGCUGGGAGAGAGGCGUCCCAGUGUCCCCCAUGCACUGACCAGCACUGCCGCCCUCCUGACCUCCAAGGAGAACCUCCCAUAUGUCCUCUGAGCUCGGCUUCCAAGGCCAGUGGAACUUGUGCCCCUGUCCAGGCGGCUGCAGCUUUGAACACACUGUCCACGCCCGCUUUCUUGUGGAGGGUGUGGGCUAUGGGUCACCUGCUGCCUGGAGGAGGGGCCCUUACCCACCCCGCCUGCAGCCACCUCUCAGGACCAGCCCCGGGGCUGGCCGAGCUCCUCUGGCCAUGCAUCCAGCCUGCUGUUCUGGGGACGUGAGCAUCACCUGAGGGUCUCAGGAAUGACGCUUGGACAUGGUGAUCAGCUGCCUGGUGGCUGCAGGAGGAAGAACCUCACUCCUACCUCAGCCCUCAGCCUGCGCUCCCCUCCUCAGUACACGGCCAAUCUGUUGCAUAAAUACACUUGAGCAUUUUGCAA